AUACCCUGCUGGGCAAAGGAGGAAGAGCCAGAGGAUCCAGACGCCUUGGAGGACUUGGAACACCUGUAACAGGACAAGGAGUUCUGCUCAGGCACGUGGCCACAGAAAACUACUUAGGAAGCCUGUGGUGAGAACAACAACAGUGCCUGAGAAUCCCACGGCUCUGGGGAAGUGAGCCCCGAGGAUGAGGCUGCUCGCCUGGCUGAUUUUCCUGGCUAACUGGGGAGGUGCCAGGGCUGAACCAGAGGAAGCGCAAGGACCAUGUGCCCAAGAGAAAGGCAAAGGGCCUCCCCCAACAUCCAUCCUGGCCAGCCUGGCUCCGGGCUUGGAAGCAGGGAAGUUCUGGCACAUCGCUGACCUGCACCUUGACCCUGACUACAAGGUAUCCAAAGACCCCUUCCAGGUGUGCCCAUCAGCUGGAUCCCAGCCAGUGCCCGACGCAGGCCCCUGGGGUGACUACCUCUGUGAUUCUCCCUGGGCCCUCAUCAACUCCUCCAUCUAUGCCAUGAAGGAGAUUGAGCCAGAGCCAGACUUCAUUCUCUGGACUGGUGAUGACACGCCUCAUGUGCCCGAUGAGAAACUGGGAGAGGCAGCUGUACUGGAAAUUGUGGAACGCCUGACCAAGCUCAUCAGAGAGGUCUUUCCAGAUACUAAAGUCUAUGCUGCUUUGGGAAAUCAUGAUUUUCACCCCAAAAACCAGUUCCCAGCUGGAAGUAACAACAUCUACAAUCAGAUAGCAGAACUAUGGAAACCCUGGCUUAGUAAUGAGUCCAUCGCUCUCUUCAAAAAAGGUGCCUUCUACUGUGAGAAGCUGCCGGGUCCCAGCGGGGCUGGGCGAAUUGUGGUCCUCAACACCAAUCUGUACUAUACCAGCAAUGCGCUGACAGCAGACAUGGCGGACCCUGGCCAGCAGUUCCAGUGGCUGGAAGAUGUGCUGACCGAUGCAUCCAAAGCUGGGGACAUGGUGUACAUUGUCGGCCACGUGCCCCCGGGGUUCUUUGAGAAGACGCAAAACAAGGCAUGGUUCCGGGAGGGCUUCAAUGAAAAAUACCUGAAGGUGGUCCGGAAGCAUCAUCGCGUCAUAGCAGGGCAGUUCUUCGGGCACCACCACACCGACAGCUUUCGGAUGCUCUAUGAUGAUGCAGGUGUCCCCAUAAGCGCCAUGUUCAUCACACCUGGAGUCACCCCAUGGAAAACCACAUUACCUGGAGUGGUCAAUGGGGCCAACAAUCCAGCCAUCCGGGUGUUCGAAUAUGACCGAGCCACACUGAGCCUGAAGGACAUGGUGACCUACUUCAUGAACCUGAGCCAGGCGAAUGCUCAGGGGACGCCGCGCUGGGAGCUCGAGUACCAGCUGACCGAGGCCUAUGGGGUGCCGGACGCCAGCGCCCACUCCAUGCACACAGUGCUGGACCGCAUCGCUGGCGACCAGAGCACACUGCAGCGCUACUACGUCUAUAACUCAGUCAGCUACUCUGCUGGGGUCUGCGACGAGGCCUGCAGCAUGCAGCACGUGUGUGCCAUGCGCCAGGUGGACAUUGACGCUUACACCACCUGUCUGUAUGCCUCUGGCACCACGCCCGUGCCCCAGCUCCCGCUGCUGCUGAUGGCCCUGCUGGGCCUGUGCACGCUCGUGCUGUGACCUGCCAGGCUCACCUUCUUCCUGGUAACGGGUAACGGGGGCAGCGCCCAGGAUCACCCAGAGCUGGGCCUUCCACCAUUUCCUCCGCGCCUGAGGAGUGAACUGAAAUAGGACAACCGAAUCAGGAAGCGAAGCCCCAGGAGCUGCAGCCAUCCGUGAUCGCGCCACUGCACUCCAGCCUGGGUGACAAAGCCAGACUCUCUCCAAAAACAAACCAGAAACAGAAAAGAAAUGACGACCCAAGACCCCCCUACAAGCAUACUUCUUUUGCGUAUUAUGUUUAACUCACAAAACAAAGCUCAUCAUGCGUUUGA